AUGGGGAUUAAAUAAAUUAAUGCACAUAAGGACAGUUUCCAGUGUAUAAUAAGUGCUAGCAAUUAAUACUGUAAUUAAUAUAUAACAAUACCCUCACUGGUCUUCUGGCUUCUACUCUGCCUUCUUAAAAUCAUGGUUCUUGAAAAUAGCUGUGGCCCUAGAGGUUGGGCGCGGUGGCUCACACCUGAAAUCCCAGCACCAUGGGAGGCCGAAGUGGGCGGAUCACCUGAGGUCAGGAGUUUGAGACCAGCCUGGCCAACAUGGUGAAACUCCAUCUUUACCAAAAAUACAAAAAAAAAAAAAAAAAUUAGCCAGGCGUGGUGACGGGCACCUGUAAUCCCAGCUACUCAGGACGUUGAAGCAGGAGAAUCACUUGAACCUGGGAGGUGGAGGUUACAGUGGGCUGAUAUCUCGCCACUGCACACCAGCUUGGGUGACAGAGCAAGACUCCGUGCAAAAAAAGAAAGAGGUGGGCACAGUGGCUCACCCCUGUAAUCCCAGCACUUUGGGAGGCCAAGACGGGUGGAUCACGAGGUCAGGAGAUCGAGACCAGCCUGGCCAACAUGGUGAAACCCUGUCUCUACUAAAAAUACAAAAAUUAGCUGGGUGUUGUGGUGAACACCUGUAAUCCCAGCUACUUGGGAGGCUGAAGCAGGAGAAUCGCUUGAACUCGGGAGGCAGAGGUUGCAGUGAGCCAAGAUUGCGCCACUGCACUCCAGCCUGGGGGACACAGCGAGAUUCCAUCUCAAAAAAAAGAGAGAGAGAGAGACCGAAGUGUCACUUCAAACUAAUACAAUGUGUGGAGCUCAUUUAGAUCUUAAGUCAAGCAAAUCAAGUGUAAUAAAAAGAUAUUUAUGAGAUAUGAUGUUUGACAUUUAGCUUCAGAAUCAUUUGGGAAGAGUGGAUGGGGGGUAAAUCAAACAAUACUGGUCAUGAGUGAAUAAUUAUUUUAAAAACUUUUUUUUUAAAGAUACGGGGUAUCACUCUGUUGCGCAGGCUGGAAUGCAGUAACACAAUCAUAGCUCAUUGCAGACAUGAACUCCUGGGUCCCCCCUCUAUCCUCCACGGCCCCAUCCAAGCCAGGGAUGAAAUUUAACGGCAAGAAGGGCGCAGUUGACGCGGCGUCAAUGAACUGAGACUAAGUCAAAAGCCGGGCCCUCCAACCCUAUCCCCAUCAGCCUGGUCAUCACCGGCGUCACCCCCGCCCCGCGCCCUGCCCCUAGGUUCCUGUGCCAGCAAGAUGCUGGAGCGAGGCGCGGAGUCCGCGGCCGGGGCUACCGAUCCUAGUCCCACUGGCAAGGAACCAGUGACCAAAGAAGCUCCCCACCAGGGCCCACCGCAGAAGCCCAGCCAGUCAGCUCCAGGGCCCACCGCGUCCGCGGGCUCGCCUCCCCGGCCUCGCCGGCGGCCCCCGCCCCAGCGCCCGCACCGCUGCCCCGACUGUGACAAGGCCUUCUCGUACCCGUCCAAGCUGGCCACGCACCGCUUAGCACACGGAGGCGCCCGACCCCACCCAUGCCCAGACUGCCCCAAGGCCUUCUCCUACCCCUCCAAGCUGGCAGCCCACCGCCUCACGCACAGCGGCGCCCGCCCGCACCCGUGCCCACACUGCCCGAAGUCCUUUGGCCACCGCUCCAAGCUGGCGGCUCACCUCUGGACCCACGCACCCACCCGCCCCUACCCGUGCCCCGACUGCCCCAAGUCCUUCUGCUACCCUUCCAAGCUGGCGGCCCACCGCCACACGCACCACGCCACCGACGCCCGCCCCUAUCCUUGCCCGCAUUGCCCCAAGGCUUUCUCAUUUCCCUCCAAGCUGGCCGCCCAUCGCCUAUGUCACGACCCCCCAACCGCGCCCGGCAGCCAGGCGACUGCCUGGCACCGAUGCUCCAGCUGCGGCCAGGCCUUUGGCCAGAGACGCUUACUGCUCCUUCAUCAACGCAGCCACCACCAGGUGGAGCACAAGGGGGAGAGAGACUGAGCCCUCCCUUGGCUCACUGUCCCCUUCUGCCGCCAGCCCUAGCCAGUAAGAGGUGGGAUUUCUAAGACCGACUGUAUGAGCUCGCCUCUUCCAGAUAGCUGGCAGAGGGCAGGGCAAGGGAUUGGCCAUUUAUACUGGGCUCGAGCUCAGAAGCCCGAGGAACUCUUUGCUCCCCUGCUUUGGGGAGAUCUCAAACCAUGGACGUGGAGCUGUGGUUUGACAGCGCUGGCUCUGCUUCUCCCCACACACUUACAUGGCAAAGGUAAAAAGUCUGCUACUAUCGUGGGUUGAUGAGGAUUGUGGGCAAACAGGCUCUCUUGUUAAAAGUUUAAACUGGUGUCUCCACUUUGGCCAUAUGACGGUAUCUAAGAAAUUGAAAAUACAUACAUGCUUGUCUCAA